CUUCAGAUAGAUUAUAUCUGGAGUGAAGAAUCCUGCCACCUAUGUAUCUGGCAUAGUAUUCUGUGUAGUGGGAUGAGCAGAGAACAAAAACAAAAUAAUCCAGUGAGAAAAGCCCGUAAAUAAACCUUCAGACCAGAGAUCUAUUCUCUAGCUUAUUUUAAGCUCAACUUAAAAAGAAGAACUGUUCUCUGAUUCUUUUCGCCUUCAAUACACUUAAUGAUUUAACUCCACCCUCCUUCAAAAGAAACAGCAUUUCCUACUUUUAUACUGUCUAUAUGAUUGAUUUGCACAGCUCAUCUGGCCAGAAGAGCUGAGACAUCCGUUCCCCUACAAGAAACUCUCCCCGGGUGGAACAAGAUGGAUUAUCAAGUGUCAAGUCCAAUCUAUGACAUCAAUUAUUAUACAUCGGAGCCCUGCCAAAAAAUCAAUGUGAAGCAAAUCGCAGCCCGCCUCCUGCCUCCGCUCUACUCACUGGUGUUCAUCUUUGGUUUUGUGGGCAACAUGCUGGUCAUCCUCAUCCUGAUAAACUGCAAAAGGCUGAAGAGCAUGACUGACAUCUACCUGCUCAACCUGGCCAUCUCUGACCUGUUUUUCCUUCUUACUGUCCCCUUCUGGGCUCACUAUGCUGCCGCCCAGUGGGACUUUGGAAAUACAAUGUGUCAACUCUUGACAGGGCUCUAUUUUAUAGGCUUCUUCUCUGGAAUCUUCUUCAUCAUCCUCCUGACAAUCGAUAGGUACCUGGCUGUCGUCCAUGCUGUGUUUGCUUUAAAAGCCAGGACGGUCACCUUUGGGGUGGUGACAAGUGUGAUCACUUGGGUGGUGGCUGUGUUUGCGUCUCUCCCAGGAAUCAUCUUUACCAGAUCUCAAAAAGAAGGUCUUCAUUACACCUGCAGCUCUCAUUUUCCAUACAGUCAGUAUCAAUUCUGGAAGAAUUUCCAGACAUUAAAGAUAGUCAUCUUGGGGCUGGUCCUGCCGCUGCUUGUCAUGGUCAUCUGCUACUCGGGAAUCCUAAAAACUCUGCUUCGGUGUCGAAAUGAGAAGAAGAGGCACAGGGCUGUGAGGCUUAUCUUCACCAUCAUGAUUGUUUAUUUUCUCUUCUGGGCUCCCUACAACAUUGUCCUUCUCCUGAACACCUUCCAGGAAUUCUUUGGCCUGAAUAAUUGCAGUAGCUCUAACAGGUUGGACCAAGCUAUGCAGGUGACAGAGACUCUUGGGAUGACGCACUGCUGCAUCAACCCCAUCAUCUAUGCCUUUGUCGGGGAGAAGUUCAGAAACUACCUCUUAGUCUUCUUCCAAAAGCACAUUGCCAAACGCUUCUGCAAAUGCUGUUCUAUUUUCCAGCAAGAGGCUCCCGAGCGAGCAAGCUCAGUUUACACCCGAUCCACUGGGGAGCAGGAAAUAUCUGUGGGCUUGUGACACGGACUCAAGUGGGCUGGUGACCCAGUCAGAGUUGUGCACAUGGCUUAGUUUUCAUACACAGCCUGGGCUGGGGGUGGGGUGGGAGAGGUCUUUUUUAAAAGGAAGUUACUGUUAUAGAGGGUCUAAGAUUCAUCCAUUUAUUUGGCAUCUGUUUAAAGUAGAUUAGAUCUUUUAAGCCCAUCAAUUAUAGAAAGCCAAAUCAAAAUAUGUUGAUGAAAAAUAGCAACCUUUUUAUCUCCCCUUCACAUGCAUCAAGUUAUUGACAAACUCUCCCUUCACUCCGAAAGUUCCUUAUGUAUAUUUAAAAGAAAGCCUCAGAGAAUUGCUGAUUCUUGAGUUUAGUGAUCUGAACAGAAAUACCAAAAUUAUUUCAGAAAUGUACAACUUUUUACCUAGUACAAGGCAACAUAUAGGUUGUAAAUGUGUUUAAAACAGGUCUUUGUCUUGCUAUGGGGAGAAAAGACAUGAAUAUGAUUAGUAAAGAAAUGACACUUUUCAUGUGUGAUUUCCCCUCCAAGGUAUGGUUAAUAAGUUUCACUGACUUAGAACCAGGCGAGAGACUUGUGGCCUGGGAGAGCUGGGGAAGCUUCUUAAAUGAGAAGGAAUUUGAGUUGGAUCAUCUAUUGCUGGCAAAGACAGAAGCCUCACUGCAAGCACUGCAUGGGCAAGCUUGGCUGUAGAAGGAGACAGAGCUGGUUGGGAAGACAUGGGGAGGAAGGACAAGGCUAGAUCAUGAAGAACCUUGACGGCAUUGCUCCGUCUAAGUCAUGAGCUGAGCAGGGAGAUCCUGGUUGGUGUUGCAGAAGGUUUACUCUGUGGCCAAAGGAGGGUCAGGAAGGAUGAGCAUUUAGGGCAAGGAGACCACCAACAGCCCUCAGGUCAGGGUGAGGAUGGCCUCUGCUAAGCUCAAGGCGUGAGGAUGGGAAGGAGGGAGGUAUUCGUAAGGAUGGGAAGGAGGGAGGUAUUCGUGCAGCAUAUGAGGAUGCAGAGUCAGCAGAACUGGGGUGGAUUUGGGUUGGAAGUGAGGGUCAGAGAGGAGUCAGAGAGAAUCCCUAGUCUUCAAGCAGAUUGGAGAAACCCUUGAAAAGACAUCAAGCACAGAAGGAGGAGGAGGAGGUUUAGGUCAAGAAGAAGAUGGAUUGGUGUAAAAGGAUGGGUCUGGUUUGCAGAGCUUGAACACAGUCUCACCCAGACUCCAGGCUGUCUUUCACUGAAUGCUUCUGACUUCAUAGAUUUCCUUCCCAUCCCAGCUGAAAUACUGAGGGGUCUCCAGGAGGAGACUAGAUUUAUGAAUACACGAGGUAUGAGGUCUAGGAACAUACUUCAGCUCACACAUGAGAUCUAGGUGAGGAUUGAUUACCUAGUAGUCAUUUCAUGGGUUGUUGGGAGGAUUCUAUGAGGCAACCACAGGCAGCAUUUAGCACAUACUACACAUUCAAUAAGCAUCAAACUCUUAGUUACUCAUUCAGGGAUAGCACUGAGCAAAGCAUUGAGCAAAGGGGUCCCAUAGAGGUGAGGGAAGCCUGAAAAACUAAGAUGCUGCCUGCCCAGUGCACACAAGUGUAGGUAUCAUUUUCUGCAUUUAACCGUCAAUAGGCAAAGGGGGGAAGGGACAUAUUCAUUUGGAAAUAAGCUGCCUUGAGCCUUAAAACCCACAAAAGUACAAUUUACCAGCCUCCGUAUUUCAGACUGAAUGGGGGUGGGGGGGGCGCCUUAGGUACUUAUUCCAGAUGCCUUCUCCAGACAAACCAGAAGCAACAGAAAAAAUCGUCUCUCCCUCCCUUUGAAAUGAAUAUACCCCUUAGUGUUUGGGUAUAUUCAUUUCAAAGGGAGAGAGAGAGGUUUUUUUCUGUUCUGUCUCAUAUGAUUGUGCACAUACUUGAGACUGUUUUGAAUUUGGGGGAUGGCUAAAACCAUCAUAGUACAGGUAAGGUGAGGGAAUAGUAAGUGGUGAGAACUACUCAGGGAAUGAAGGUGUCAGAAUAAUAAGAGGUGCUACUGACUUUCUCAGCCUCUGAAUAUGAACGGUGAGCAUUGUGGCUGUCAGCAGGAAGCAACGAAGGGAAAUGUCUUUCCUUUUGCUCUUAAGUUGUGGAGAGUGCAACAGUAGCAUAGGACCCUACCCUCUGGGCCAAGUCAAAGACAUUCUGACAUCUUAGUAUUUGCAUAUUCUUAUGUAUGUGAAAGUUACAAAUUGCUUGAAAGAAAAUAUGCAUCUAAUAAAAAACACCUUCUAAAAUAA